AUUGUUCCGCCGGUCGCGCCGGAGCUGGGUUGCUCCUGCUCCCGUCUCCAAGUCCUGGUACCUCCUUCAAGCUGGGAGAGGGCUCUAGUCCCUGGUUCUGAACACUCUGGGGUUCUCGGGUGCAGGCCGCCAUGAGCAAACGGAAGGCGCCGCAGGAGACUCUCAACGGGGGAAUCACCGACAUGCUCACAGAACUCGCAAACUUUGAGAAGAACGUGAGCCAAGCUAUCCACAAGUACAAUGCUUACAGAAAAGCAGCAUCUGUUAUAGCAAAAUACCCACACAAAAUAAAGAGUGGAGCUGAAGCUAAGAAAUUGCCUGGAGUAGGAACAAAAAUUGCUGAAAAGAUUGAUGAGUUUUUAGCAACUGGAAAAUUACGUAAACUGGAAAAGAUUCGGCAGGAUGAUACGAGUUCAUCCAUCAAUUUCCUGACUCGAGUUAGUGGCAUUGGUCCAUCUGCUGCAAGGAAGUUUGUAGAUGAAGGAAUUAAAACACUAGAAGGCUCACAGCUGGAUUCAUGCCCAGUAAAGGGACACCUGAAUGGAACUGAGUCACUUUUAGACUUAAUAUGGGAUGUUAUGACAAUUCUUAAGUUAAAAAAUGCAGAUCUCAGAAAAAAUGAAGAUAAAUUGAACCAUCAUCAGCGAAUUGGGCUGAAAUAUUUUGGGGACUUUGAAAAAAGAAUUCCUCGUGAAGAGAUGUUACAAAUGCAAGAUAUUGUACUAAAUGAAGUUAAAAAAGUGGAUUCUGAAUACAUUGCUACAGUCUGUGGCAGUUUCAGAAGAGGUGCAGAGUCCAGUGGUGACAUGGAUGUUCUCCUGACCCAUCCCAGCUUCACUUCAGAAUCAACCAAACAGCCAAAACUGUUACAUCAGGUUGUGGAGCAGUUACAAAAGGUUCAUUUUAUCACAGAUACCCUGUCAAAGGGUGAGACAAAGUUCAUGGGUGUUUGCCAGCUUCCCAGUAAAAAUGAUGAAAAAGAAUAUCCACACAGAAGAAUUGAUAUCAGGUUGAUACCCAAAGAUCAGUAUUACUGUGGUGUUCUCUAUUUCACUGGGAGUGAUAUUUUCAAUAAGAAUAUGAGGGCUCAUGCCCUAGAAAAGGGUUUCACAAUCAAUGAGUACACCAUCCGUCCCUUGGGAGUCACUGGAGUUGCAGGAGAACCCCUGCCAGUGGAUAGUGAAAAAGACAUCUUUGAUUACAUCCAGUGGAAAUACCGGGAACCCAAGGACCGGAGCGAAUGAGGCCUGUAUCCUCCCUGGCAGACACAACCCAAUAGGAGUCUUAAUUUAUUUCUUAACCUUUGCUAUGUAAGGGUCUUUGGUGUUUUUAAAUGAUUGUUUCUUCUUCAUGCUUUUGCUUGCAAUGUAGUCAAUAAAACCUCAUGUACUAUUA